AGUUUCAGCGCUGGCUCUUCGUGCAUGGCAGAGAUGGCGACUGCGACUCGGCUGCUGGGGUGGCGUGUGGCGAGCUGGAGGCUGCGGCCGCCGCUUGCCGGCUUCGUUUCCCAGCGGGCCCACUCGCUUUUGCCCGUGGACGAUGCAAUCAAUGGGCUAAGCGAGGAGCAGAGGCAGGUGAGGAGACUGACCCCCUUCCUGGCCCCAAGGCCUCCUUCCUGCCUGGUCCCCAAGGCCUCCUUCCUGCCUGGUCCCCAUCGGCCCAGCGCCCACCCAGCCUUGGCUUUUGCCCGUGGGCCGUUGGGAGCGCCAGCGCGGGGGCGGGACGCGGGGCCUCCGACCUCGGGUCCAGUCCUCUGACCUCGGCCUCACGUCUGUGGAGUGAAGAUUUGAGACCGUGGGACAGUACUGCUGGAAGUAGAGAGGAGGAGUCGAGGCUGGGAGAGCUCCUGAGAGACUGAUGGUGUUUUGGUGGAGGAUUGGCCAGGCUACCUACCGCUUGUGGCACAAGGGCCCUCAAUCUGUAUGUAGUUCACUUACACCUGAACAGGCUGAGCUUCGUCAGACCAUGGCUAAGUUCCUUCAGGAGCACCUGGCCCCCAAGGCCCAGGAGAUCGAUCGCAGCAAUGAGUUCAAGAACCUGCGAGUGAGUUGGGAGGUCCGGGCAGUCGGGGGCAGUCAGGGAGUGGGGCUGAGCUGCACUGCUGCCUGGAAGAGCUCACACAGUUUUCUGGAAUUUUGGAAGCAGCUGGGGAACCUGGGCGUAUUGGGCAUCACAGCCCCUGUUCAGUAUGGCGGCUCCGGCCUGGGCUACCUGGAGCAUGUGCUGGUGAUGGAGGAGAUAUCCCGAGCUUCCGGAGCAGUGGGGCUCAGUUACGGUGCCCACUCCAACCUCUGCAUCAACCAGCUUGUACGCAAUGGGAAUGAGGCCCAGAAAGAGAAGUAUCUCCCGAAGCUGAUCAGUGGUGAGUACAUCGGAGCCCUGGCCAUGAGUGAGCCCAAUGCAGGCUCUGAUGUUGUCUCUAUGAAGCUCAAAGCGGAAAAGAAAGGAAAUCACUACAUCCUGAAUGGCAACAAGUUCUGGAUCACUAAUGGCCCUGAUGCUGACGUCCUGAUUGUCUAUGCCAAGACAGAUCUGGCUGCUGUGCCAGCUUCUCGGGGCAUCACAGCCUUCAUUGUGGAGAAGGGUAUGCCUGGCUUUAGCACCUCUAAGAAGCUGGACAAGCUGGGGAUGAGGGGCUCUAACACCUGUGAGCUAAUCUUUGAAGACUGCAAGAUUCCUGCUGCCAACAUCCUGGGCCAUGAGAAUAAGGGUGUCUACGUGCUGAUGAGUGGGCUGGACCUGGAGCGGCUGGUGCUGGCCGGGGGGCCUCUUGGGCUCAUGCAAGCGGUCCUGGACCACACCAUUCCCUACCUGCACGUGAGGGAAGCCUUUGGCCAGAAGAUCGGCCACUUCCAGUUGAUGCAGGGGAAGAUGGCUGACAUGUACACCCGCCUCAUGGCGUGUCGGCAGUAUGUCUACAAUGUCGCCAAGGCCUGCGAUGAGGGCCAUUGCACUGCUAAGGACUGUGCAGGUGUGAUUCUUUACUCAGCUGAGUGUGCCACACAGGUAGCCCUGGACGGCAUUCAGUGUUUUGGUGGCAAUGGCUACAUCAAUGACUUUCCCAUGGGCCGCUUUCUUCGAGAUGCCAAGCUGUAUGAGAUAGGGGCUGGGACCAGCGAGGUGAGGCGGCUGGUCAUCGGCAGAGCCUUCAAUGCAGACUUUCACUAGUCCUGAGACCCUUCGCCCCCUUUUCCUGCACCUAGUGGCCUUUCUUGGGAAGUAGAGAUGUGGCGGCUUUCCCACCCUGCCCACAGCAGGCCCUCCUGCCCAGCUGCUCUUGUCAGCCCUCUGGCCUCUGGAUGAGGUUGAGUUCUCCACAACAGCUCCCAAGCAUCAUGGGCCUCGCAGCCGGGCCUGUGCCACGGCUAGUGUUGUGUGAUUUAAAAUGGACUCAGCAGGAAGCAUAUUGUCUGGGGAUUGUUGGGACAGGUUUUGGUGACUCUGUGCCCUUGCUCUCUAACUUCUGAGCCCACCUCCCAGGGUAGGCACCUGGGGGCAUGCAGGUGCCCACCUCCCAGGGUAGGCACCUGGGGGCAUGCAGGUACCCACCUCUUUCUCUUGGGUGAGGCUCUGGCAAGGAGAUCUCUCUGCUCAAGCACAGCAGAAUCAUGGCCCCUCUCCAUGAAUUGGAACUUGGUACAGGUUAAGUAUCCCUAAUCCUGAAAUCUGAAACACUUGUGGUUCCAAGCAUUUUGGAUAAGGCAAAUUCAACUUUCAGUCUCUUUUCUGGGGGAAAAAAAUAAUAAACCUAGCCUAGCCAGGCGUGGUGGCUCAUGCUUGUAAUCCCAGCACUUCAGGAGGCUGAGAUGGGUGGAUCACCUGAGGUCAGGAGUUCAAGACCAGCCUGGCCAACAUGUGGAAACCUCGCCUCAACUAAAAAUAGAAAAAAAUUAGUUGGGCAUGGUGGUGGGCACCUGUAAUCCCAGCUACUUCAGGAGGCUGAGGCAGGAGAAUUACUUGAACCCAGGAGGCGGACGUUGCAGUGAGCCGAGCUUGUGCCAUUGCACUCCAGCCUGGGCGACAAGAGCAAAACUCUUCAAAAAACAAAACAAAACAAAAAAACCCUGGCCCUUGUUUCUUCCAGUUUCUAGAGGUAUCAGCUCCUAGCAGCUUAUGAACACAUAUGCUUGCUUGGCCAGGCAAGGUGGUGUGUGCCUGUAAUCCCAGCACUUUGGGAGGCCAAGGCAGGUGGAUCACUUGCAGUCAGGAGUUCAAGACCAGCCUGUCCAACGUGGUGAAACCCCAUCUCUACUAAAAAUACAAAAAUUAGCCAGGGGUGGUGGUGCACGUCUGUAAUCCCAGCUACUCAGGAGGCUGAGGCAGGAGAAUCACUUGAACCCGGGAGGUGGAGGUUGCAAUGAGCCAAUAUGACACCGCUGCAGUCCAGCCUGGGCCAUAGAGUGAGACUCUGUCUCAAAAAAGGAAAGAAAAAUAGGCUGGGCACAGUGACUCAUGCCUGUAAUCCCAACACUUUGGGAGGCCGAGGCAGGUGGAUCACGAGGUCAGGAGUUCAAGACCAGCCUGGCCAAGAUGGUAAAACCUCGUCUCUACUAAAAAUACAAAAAUUAGCCAGGUGUGGUGGCAGGCUCCUGUAAUCCCAGCUACUCAGGAGGCUGAGGCAGAGAAUUGCUUGAACCCGGGAGGCAGAGUUUGCAGUGAGCCAAGAUCACACCACUGCACUCCAGCUUGGACGACAGAGCGAGACUCUGUCUCAAAAAAUAAUAGGCCAGGCAUGGUGGCUCAACGUCUGUAAUCCCAGCACUUUGGGAGGCCGAGGCGGGCAGAUCACAAGGUCAGGAGUUCGAGACCAGCCUGACGACCAACAUGGUGAAACCUCGUCUCUACUAAAAAUACAAAAAUUAGCCAGGCCUGGUGGCACGCGCCUGUAAUCCCAGUUACACAGAAGACUGAGGCAGGAGAAUCGCUUGAACGCAGGAGGCAGAGGUUGCAGGAGCUGAGAUCGCGCCAUUGCACUCCAGCCUGGGCAACAGAGUGAGACUCUGUCUCAAAAAAUAAUAAUAAAAUAAAUGAACACACAUGCUGCUGAGUCCGCAGGGGGGGCAGAGCAGAGGACAGCGUGCUUUUGUGUACUGUUGGAAGACUGGCUCCUCCUGUACAGCACCUCUGAGCCCUUGUGCACCGCCCUGCCACGGGCACCAUCCAGUCCUGGCCGUGUGACCACCCACAGCUGACUGGGCAGCAGGCACAGGCCCUACCCGAGCAGGCCGGAGUUGGCUCGCAUGACUCCAGCUGAGGCUGCCUGUGUACAUUUCUCCAGAUACCCUAUGGCUAAUUUUGUUAUAACUGCACAGUGGCUGCUGCCAUUUUGUAUUAAAUAUAUUGUGAAACAAACCUAUCUGGGGAGAAGCAAUCUACUUGCCGCUGCUUCCUGUCUGGAUCCAGCUUGUGUCCUUGGAGAGUGGCUGGCCCAGGUCCUAUUCCUGUCCUCCAGCCCGUUCUUUCAUGAGGGACAGGAAGGUAAAAUCAGCCCUUAGGAGAGAGGUCUCAGCCUCCCUUUCCCAGAUCUCCCAGUGAGUUUUAAAGGAAGCAGGGAGCCCAGAGUGCUAAGUUCUUACAGCCAGAAGGAAGCUUAUAGAUUUCUGAAAACCGCCCCUUUGUUUUUAAAAAGAUCAACACAAUUUGACUUUCUCAAGGUCAAAACGAACUAGAAUCCAGAUCUGCUCAUGGCAAAAAUGGGGGUGUUCUGAGAAUUCCAGCUUUGGGCCGCACUGUACAGCAGUCUGGAUAGAGUGUGAUCUGAGAAGGGAAUGGGUCUGGGUUGUUCCACCCCUUCCGAGUUCCAAAAAGAGGGAACUGGUUUUCUUGGUUCUCAGCCCAGCAGCACCUAUCCUGGCUCUUGGUCCUGGCCUGCAGCCAAGUGCUGUUCCUAGCCUGAGGCUUGAGACAGGUGGGGUUGGCUCCUCACCAACCCCAGUUCCGUCCCAUCCUGAGGGCAAGAUCCUGGGCUCAUAGGCAGUCCCUUUCACUUCCUUGUCUUGCUCCCUGCUAUGUUGGAGAUGAAUGUGACUAAAAGGGCCAUCUUGCUGGCUUAAUGUGUGGCUGGAGAGACCAGCCUGGAGACAAUGUGGCAAAAUGGGGCGCUUCAUCCAGUCUGUCUAAGCCCUGUCGACUUGGGGAGGUGAUUUCUUUCCUGGUUCUAUAUGUGAAGCAAAAUAAAUGUUUUAAAAUUAAAAGCAAAAAAAACAAAAUGAA